GAAGCAGGCUGCUCGCCUCCUGCCUGUAGUGUGUGGGCUGGGGUUGGUGCGAGCUUCCAGCUUGGCCGCAGUUGGUUCGUAGUUCGGCUCUGGGGUCUUUUGUGUCCGGGUCUGGCUUGGCUUUGUGUCCGCGAGUUUUUGUUCCGCUCCGCAGCGCUCUUCCCGGGCAGGAGCCGUGAGGCUCGGAGGCGGCAGCGCGGUCCCCGGCCAGGAGCAAGCGCGCCGGCGUGAGCGGCGGCGGCAAAGGCUGUGGGGAGGGGGCUUCGCAGAUCCCCGAGAUGCCGGAGUUCCUGGAAGACCCCUCGGUCCUGACAAAAGACAAGUUGAAGAGUGAGUUGGUCGCCAACAAUGUGACGCUGCCGGCCGGGGAGCAGCGCAAAGACGUGUACGUCCAGCUCUACCUGCAGCACCUCACGGCUCGCAACCGGCCGCCGCUCCCCGCCGGCACCAACAGCAAGGGGCCCCCGGACUUCUCCAGUGACGAAGAGCGCGAGCCCACCCCGGUCCUCGGCUCUGGGGCCGCCGCCGCGGGCCGGAGCCGAGCAGCCGUCGGCAGGAAAGCCACAAAAAAAACUGAUAAACCCAGACAAGAAGAUAAAGAUGAUCUAGAUGUAACAGAGCUCACUAAUGAAGAUCUUUUGGAUCAGCUUGUGAAAUACGGAGUGAAUCCUGGUCCUAUUGUGGGAACAACCAGGAAGCUAUAUGAGAAAAAGCUUUUGAAACUGAGGGAACAAGGAACAGAAUCAAGAUCUUCUACUCCUCUGCCAACAAUUUCUUCUUCAGCAGAAAAUACAAGGCAGAAUGGAAGUAAUGAUUCUGACAGAUACAGUGACAAUGAAGAAGACUCUAAAAUAGAGCUCAAGCUUGAGAAGAGAGAACCACUAAAGGGCAGAGCAAAGACUCCAGUAACACUCAAGCAAAGAAGAGUUGAGCACAAUCAGAGCUAUUCUCAAGCUGGAAUAACUGAGACUGAAUGGACAAGUGGAUCUUCAAAAGGCGGACCUCUGCAGGCAUUAACUAGGGAAUCUACAAGAGGGUCAAGAAGAACUCCAAGGAAAAGGGUGGAAACUUCAGAACAUUUUCGUAUAGAUGGUCCAGUAAUUUCAGAGAGUACUCCCAUAGCUGAAACUAUAAUGGCUUCAAGCAACGAAUCCUUAGUUGUCAAUAGGGUGACUGGAAAUUUCAAGCAUGCAUCUCCUAUUCUGCCAAUCACUGAAUUCUCAGACAUACCCAGAAGAGCACCAAAGAAACCAUUGACAAGAGCUGAAGUGGGAGAAAAAACAGAGGAAAGAAGAGUAGAAAGGGAUAUUCUUAAGGAAAUGUUCCCCUAUGAAGCAUCUACACCAACAGGAAUUAGUGCUAGUUGCCGCAGACCAAUCAAAGGGGCUGCAGGCCGGCCAUUAGAACUCAGUGAUUUCAGGAUGGAGGAGUCUUUUUCAUCUAAAUAUGUUCCUAAGUAUGUUCCCUUGGCAGAUGUCAAGUCAGAAAAGACAAAAAAGGGACGCUCCAUUCCCGUAUGGAUAAAAAUUUUGCUGUUUGUUGUUGUGGCAGUUUUUUUGUUUUUGGUCUAUCAAGCUAUGGAAACCAACCAAGUAAAUCCCUUCUCUAAUUUUCUUCAUGUUGACCCUAGAAAAUCCAACUGAAUGGUAUCUCUUUGGCACGUUCAACUUGGUCUCCUAUUUUCAAUAACUGUUGAAAAACAUUUGUGUACACUUGUUGACUCCAAGAACUAAAAAUAAUGUGAUUUCGCCUCAAUAAAUGUAGUAUUUCAUUGAAAAGCAAACAAAAUAUAUAUAAAUGGACUUCAUUAAAAUGUUUUUGAACUUUGGACUAGUAGGAGAUCACUUUGUGCCAUAUGAAUAAUCUUUUUUAGCUCUGGAACUUUUUGUAGGCUUUAUUUUUUUAAUGUGGGCAUCUUAUUUCAUUUUUGAAAAAAUGUAUAUGUUUUUUGUGUAUUUGGGAAACGAAGGGUGAAACAUGGUAGUAUAAUGUGAAGCUACACAUUUAAAUACUUAGAAUUCUUACAGAAAAGAUUUUAAGAAUUAUUCUCUGCUGAAUAAAAACUGCAAAUAUGUGAAACAUAAUGAAAUUCAGUAAGAGGAAAAGUAACUUGGUUGUACUUUUUGUAACUGCAACAAAGUUUGAUGGUGUUUAUGAGGAAAAGUACAGCAAUAAUCUCUUCUGUAACCUUUAUUAAUAGUAAUGUUGUUGUAGCCCUAUCAUACUCACUUUUUAAGACACAGUAUCAUGAAAGUCCUAUUUCAGUAAGACCCAUUUACAUACAGUAGAUUUUUAGCAGAGAUCUUUUAGUGUAACAUACAUAUUUUAGAGAAUUGUUGGCUAGCUGUACAUGUUUUGAAAAGCUGUUUAGCUAGCUAUAAGGCUAUAAUUGGAAAUUUGUAUUUUUUAUUUACAGCAAAACAUUUAUUCAGUCAUCCAGUUUGCUACCAAAAUAUGUUUUAGAUAAGUGUGUGUAUGUUUGUUUAGAAGUUAGAAAUUGUAAACACUGGUCUUAUGUUUCAUUUGGAUUCAUUAUUGCAUUGUCUUGUUACCAGAAACAAAUUUUGCCGAGCUUUUUUUGCCCUAUAUUUCCCAGCAUAAUUUGAUUAGAAAGUACAAAAAGGGCCAGGCGCGGUGGCUUACGCCUGUAAUCCCAGCACUUUGGGAGGCCAGGGCGGGUGGAUCACGAGGUCAAGAGAUCAAGACCAUCCUGGCCAACAUGGUGAAACCCCGUCUCUACUAAAAAUACAAAAAAAUUAGCUGGGCGUGAUGAUGUGCGCCUGUAGUCCUGUCUACUAGGGAGACUGAGGCAGGAGAAUCGUUUGAACCCAGGAGGCAGAGGUUGCAGUGAGCAGAGAUUACGUCACUGCACUGUAGCCUGGCGACAGAGCAAGACUCCAUCUCAAAAAAAAUAAAAAAGUACAAAAAGUACUUGCUUUUAUAUUACAUCAUAAGCAGUAGUUAAUAAAGUUGUAUACUCUUAAGAGGUGGGCAUUAUGAUUAUUUUUUAUUUUUUUAUUUUUUAUGAGAUGGAGUCUCACUCUUGUCACCCAGACUGUAGUGCAGUGGCACGAUCUGGGCUCGAUGCAACCUCUGCCUCCCAGGUUCAAGCAAUUUUCCUGCCUCGGCAGAGACGGGGUUUCACCAUGUUGGCCAGGCUGGUCUCGAACCCCUGACCUCAAGUGAUCAGCCCACCUCAGCUUCCCAAAGUGCUGGGAUUACAGGUGUGAUCCACUGCACCCGGCCGGCAUUAUGAUUUUGUGUACUCUUGAAAUGGUUAUCUUUGUGGAUGAUUUUUUUUUUUAAGCUGAAACUUACCUCAUGAAUAACUUGAUUAAAGUAGUAGGUGAUUAAAAUUUCAAUAGAAUCAAAUGAGACAAAAAUUUUAAACUGACUCAUUUGAGUUUCAACUUUACAGUCAUUGACCAUAAAGCACACUAAAAAUGUAAGUUAUUUUUAAAUACAUCUGAAAUAAAAAUACUUACUAAAAAGGAAGAAGCCGAAGAUGUAUAUUUAGACCAGCACACAAUUUUGAUUUCAAUUAGCCUUAUUCUAAUAUUUAGCUUUUAGAUCUUUCAUACACAUUUUCACGUACUUUGCAAUUGAGACCAGAAAGACUUGUAGGUCUUUCUGCAGAAUGAGUGGGUCCUUGCAAAGUGAGUGGGAAACUUACUCCUAGAUCAGAAAUGUUUGCCUCUCUGAGUAAAAUGUUUCUUUCAGAUGAGCCAUAGAGGGGGCACCUUUUACUCAACUUUUCUUUGUUUUGAAACUUUGUUUCCCAUACUGUUUUCAGCCUUUUGUUUAUAAUUAGAAAUUGUGAGAAGCUUCAUUUAGUGUUUAAAAAUGUGGGGAGAUAAAUCAGACUUAACAUGUAUGUAAGAUCAAUUCACUUAAAAGUAUGGUCCAAAUAGCAAAAAUAGGACCAGGUGAAACAUGUAGUCAUUUUUUAAAAACAUGUACUUGGUCUUUUGUGUGUGUCUGUUUUAUUCCAUUAGAAUAAAUGUGUCCUUGAUGUAAAUGCAAAGCAUUUCUUCCUGAUUAAAUUGUAGAUGUAGACUUUACAAUAUAAUUCAAUAAUAAAAAGUAAUUAACCUCUAGUUUUGUCGUUGCAAUAAAUGGUUUUCAGAUAGCACAAA